UUCUUCUUUUUUUUUUUUUUUUUUUUUUUUUUGAGACAGAAUUUCGCUCAGGCUGGAGUGUAAUGGUGCGAUCUCGGCUCACUGCAACCCCCGCCUCCCGGAUUCAAGCAAUUCUCCUGCCUCAGCCCGAAGUAGCUGGGAUUACAGGCGCCUGCCACCACGCCCAGCUAAUUUUUUUGUAUUUUUAGUUGAGACGGGGUUUCCCCAUGUUGGCCAGGCUGGUUUCGAACUCCCGACCUCAGGUGGUCCGCCUGCCUUAGCCUCCCAAAGUGCUGGGAUUACAGGCGUGAGCCACCCUGCCCUGCCUUUUCUUCAUGUUUUGUUAUUAUGUUUUUUUUGGAGACAGAGUCUUACUUUGUCACCCAGGCUGGAGUGCAGUGGCGCAAUCUCAUCUCACUGCAACCUCCGCCUCCCGGGUUCAAGCUAUUCUCCUGCCUCAGCCUCCUCAGUAGCUGAGAUGACAGGCCCACGCCACCACGCCCCGCUAAUUUUUGUGUUUUUAGUAGAGACAGCAUUUUGCCAUGUUGUCAUGUUGUCCAGGCUGGUCUCAAACACCUGACCUUAGGUGAUCCGCCUUGGCCUCCUAAAGUUCUGGGAUUACAUGCCUGAGCCACCGCGCCCAGCCUUCAUCAUGUAUUCUGUUAUGUUUUAAAUGAAAGAAGCAGUAGCUUGGAACUGGAAAGGCUCUUGAGGGGGCACAGAGUCGACCUCUCCCAGGUUACUGAGGGGAGGCCAAACCUGCUCAGGCUCCUAGACUUGCCUGUGACCAAGACCAAGAAAAGCCGGGUCUUGGUCCCCAGCGCCCCCAGCCCCUGGUGUUGCUCUUCUGGCACAAGUCAAGGGAAGAGCACUAGCGGGUGAAGGGGCUGCUCACAUACAAAACCCAAGUGGGUUAGGACCAUAUCUGUAAGGCACCAUAUCUGUAAGGCAGCGCAGGCUGCCGCCGUCAGAUGAUCUCCUUAAGAGUCCGUCUAGGUGGUGGCAGAGCAUGGCUGUGGGAGCUUCCAUGCCCUUUUGUGGGCAGCUUGGGAGGGCAGCUACUUGUACUCGCCCAAACCCCAAUCAGACAGAUGCAGGCAAGUAAACAGGGUUCGAAGUCAAAAUAUGGCUUCUUGUGGACAGAAUCUGACCAAGCCCAGGUGGGGCUUUGUUUCUCUUUAUUCACAUAGUACUUAAAGCUGCCAGACCAGGCUUUUACAUGAAAAUGACCUAAUUUGAAGCCGAUAGAGGAUUACCAUGGAAGUCACUGAUCAGAUAAAGUGACACAUCCAUUUUUUCACAUCUUCAGAAAACAAGAGCAAAACUGAAGUGACAAGAUUUGACCAGAAAGUGUGGGCUGCUGAAAGCAAGACCUAAGUAAGCUUAGUUUCCCAGGCCCAGUGUCUUCCAGUAUUAUGACAAUGACAUUAAGUCUUUCACUGGGCCGGGUCCAUGAUAGACAUUCCUUUUGUGAACUUCUUGACUGUAGGAGGUUGGCCAGAGCGUCACCAUCUUCAGAUGGGCAGAGGGAGGUUGGCUGGCCGCACUGGCUUGUGGUGGCCUGGAGACUGAGUCCGCAUCCUGUUACCCCAAAGGCUGGGUUCCUCACUGCUUGGUUGACUGAUCUUUCCUUCUGGCCUGCAGAGGCUGGUCCACGGGGACGAGCAGUCUGGUUAGUUUCUGCUGGCAGGCUCCCCACAGUUGCAUCUCUUGUCUCUCUGCCUCUGGCAUCAAGCUGCUUGCUCUGGCAGCCAGGGACAGUGUCCUCUUGCUCCCAGGAGCCAUGCUCUGUAGAAACUGCUGAGACGUGCUCUAUGCAGGAGCUUGGCAUUUGGAAGCCAUGGGAAGGGUCCAGAAACUAAUGAACUCAGCAAUCCAAACUAAUGUCCAUGCCUGCAGCUGCUCCUCAUUGCCUAUUAGACACUCUGUAAAAUGUAGCUUCUAAGCAGUUUAUACCCAUAAACAGCAAUAUUAGCACUUAAUGGGUUCUGCCUGGUGGCUCAUCACCAAGGUGACAGAAAAGCUGCAUGGGGCCUUCCUCUCCAGUGUGACCUUUGGUGUUUUUAACCUGUCCUCAAGAGUGGCAGAGCUAGUCCUGGGCCCUAGGAGCUGGCCUCGGCCCUAGUUGAAGUGCUGGGGAAGCAAGGAUAGGCCUGAGGACCCCUGAACUUGCAGGUGGCACAGGCACUGUGAGGGUCCCGAUGAACACCAUGCUGGUGACUGGUGUGGCAAAGUCCUGGUGACAGUGGCAGGCUCUGUCAUACCCUGCCCUAUAUCAUGAAGGAGUGGGGAGAGAAGGCAAAGAGGAGCUGACUCACUUUUCUUUGUGUGAUGAUCUUAACGGGAGGUUAAAACUCACUCUUCAGGGGAGUGCGGGCGAGGAGCAGAGGAGGUUGUGGUUAGCGGGGCUCCUCCCAGAACAUGGGGCCCAGUCGUUCUCAGUUACGUCUUUCCUAUAGUUGGGAUUUUGAUCACACAGUUUUUUAGUAAAGCCAGGCCAUCAUCUCCCACAUUGGGCUGGCGACAUCCUUUCUGGCCCUGCAGGGUGCAGUGUGAACCUAUAGAGCAGCAUGGGAGCGGGGCUCGGGGAAGUUCUGGAGCUGCAGUGAGCCAGUGAGCUCGAGCCAGCUCUGACAGGCUGAUGUGAGGGAAGCCGCUGGGCCGCAGGUGCUUGUUUCUAGGAUGUGUGGGACCUGAGUUGGGCUUUGAACAAGGCAGCCCCAGUCCUUGGUGAUCAAGGAAAUCUGACCUGCCUUUUUCGUCGAUGUUCACAUUCACCACGAAUUUGCAAGCUGCUUUCCUCAAUUUCUUUCUGUCCUGAGUGUGAAGAGAAAGUGGAGUUUUCUGUGUGGCGUGGGAGCUGCAGGUGGCUGUGACAGUGAUCACUGGAUGCCCAGGAAGUCAUCUCAGGGUGGAUAUAAUUAAUUACGUUUCUAAAAUCCCCUUCAGUCGUCUAAAAUAACCACCCCUUUGAGAGAAAUAUCAGUCUUCCUGUUAAGCCCCUCAGAUGCUGUCACUGCUUAUGAACCAUAUCCUGCUUGAUGGCGCGGUUCUCGGAGAGACUUAAUGAGAAGCUUGGCCACAGAGCGUCUGUUCCUCACACACCCCGCCCAAGGACGUGCCUGGCAGCGGCCUGGUGCUCCCCGCCGCAGCCACCUCACCCUUGGGUUUCUGUGGCCCUGCAGUUCCUCCGUGUCACAAAGCAGUACCUGCCCCACGUGGCGCGCCUCUGUCUGAUCAGCACCUUCCUGGAGGACGGCAUCCGUAUGUGGUUCCAGUGGAGCGAGCAGCGCGACUACAUCGACACCACCUGGAACUGCGGCUACCUGCUGGCCUCGUCCUUCGUCUUCCUCAACUUGCUGGGACAGCUGACUGGCUGCGUCCUGGUGUUGAGCAGGAACUUCGUGCAGUACGCCUGCUUCGGGCUCUUUGGAAUCAUAGCUCUGCAGACGAUUGCCUACAGCAUUUUAUGGGACUUGAAGUUUUUGAUGAGGAACCUGGCCCUGGGAGGAGGCCUGUUGCUGCUCCUAGCAGAAUCCCGUUCUGAAGGGAAGAGCAUGUUUGCGGGCGUCCCCACCAUGCGUGAGAGCUCCCCCAAACAGUACAUGCAGCUCGGAGGCAGGGUCUUGCUGGUUCUGAUGUUCAUGACCCUCCUUCACUUUGACGCCAGCUUCUUUUCUAUUGUCCAGAACAUCGUGGGCACAGCUCUGAUGAUUUUAGUGGCCAUUGGUUUUAAAACCAAGCUGGCUGCUUUGACUCUUGUUGUGUGGCUCUUUGCCAUCAACGUAUAUUUCAACGCCUUCUGGACCAUUCCAGUCUACAAGCCCAUGCAUGACUUCCUGAAAUACGACUUCUUCCAGACCAUGUCGGUGAUUGGGGGCUUGCUCCUGGUGGUGGCCCUGGGCCCUGGGGGUGUCUCCAUGGAUGAGAAGAAGAAGGAGUGGUAACAGUCACAGAUCCCUACCUGCCUGGCUAAGACCCGUGGCCGUCAAGGACUGGUUCGGGGUGGAUUCAACAAAACUGCCAGCUUUUAUGUAUCCUCUUCCCUUCCCCUCCCUUGGUAAAGGCACAGAUGUUUUGAGAACUUUAUUUGCAGAGACACCUGAGAAUCGAUGGCUCAGUCUGCUCUGGAGCCACAGUCUGGCGUCUGACCCUUCAGUGCAGGCCAGCCUGGCAGCUGGAAGCCUCCCCCACGCCGAGGCUUUGGAGUGAACAGCCCGCUUGGCUGUGGCAUCUCAGUCCUAUUUUUGAGUUUUUUUGUGGGGGUACAGGAGGGGGCCUUCAAGCUGUACUGUGAGCAGACGCAUUGGUAUUAUCAUUCAAAGCAGUCUCCCUCUUAUUUGUAAGUUUACAUUUUUAGCGGAAACUACUAAAUUAUUUUGGGUGGUUCAGCCAAACCUCAAAACAGUUAAUCUCCCUGGUUUAAAAUCACACCAGUGGCUUUGAUGUUGUUUCUGCCCCGCAUUGUAUUUUAUAGGAAUAGUGAAAACAUUUAGGGACACCCAAAGAAUGAUGCAGUAUUAAAGGGGUGGUAGAAGCUGCUGUUUAUGAUAAAAGUCAUCGGUCAGAAAAUCAGCUUGGAUUGGUGCCAAGUGUUUUAUUGGGUAACACCCUGGGAGUUUUAGUAGCUUGAGGCAAGGUGGAGGGGCAAGAAGUCCUUGGGGAAGCUGCUGGUCUGGGUGCUGCUGGCCUCCAAGCUGGCAGUGGGAAGGGCUAGUGAGACCACACAGGGGUAGCCCCAGCAGCAGCACCCUGCAAGCCAGCCUGGCCAGCUGCUCAGACCAGCUUGCAGAGCCGCAGCCGCUGUGGGCAGGGGGUGUGGCAGGAGCUCCCAGCACUGGAGACCCACGGACUCAACCCAGUUACCUCACAUGGGGCCUUUUCUGAGCAAGGUCUCGAAAGCGCAGGCCGCCCUGGCUGAGCAGCACCGCCCUUUCCCAGCUGCACUCGCCCUGUGGACAGCCCCGACACACCACUUUCCUGAGGCUGUCGCUCACUCAGAUUGUCCGUUUGCUAUGCCGAAUGCAGCCAAAAUUCCUUUUUACAAUUUGUGAUGCCUUACCGAUUUGAUCUUAAUCCUGUAUUUAAAGUUUUCUAACACUGCCUUAUACUGUGUUUCUCUUUUUGGGGGAGCUUAACUGCUUGUUGCUCCCUGUCGUCUGCACCAUAGUAAAUGCCACAAGGGUAGUCGAACACCUCUCUGGCCCCUAGACCUAUCUGGGGACAGGCUGGCUCAGCCUGUCUCCAGGGCUGCUGCGGCCCAGCCCCGAGCCUGCCUCCCUCUUGGCCUCUCAUCCAUUGGCUCUGCAGGGCAGGGGUGAGGCAGGUUUCUGCUCAUAAGUGCUUUUGGAAGUCACCUACCUUUUUAACACAGCCGAACUAGUCCCAACGCGUUUGCAAAUAUUCCCCUGGUAGCCUACUUCCUUACCCCCGAAUAUUGGUAAGAUCGAGCAAUGGCUUCAGGACAUGGGUUCUCUUCUCCUGUGAUCAUUCAAGUGCUCACUGCAUGAAGACUGGCUUGUCUCAGUGUUUCAACCUCACCAGGGCUGUCUCUUGGUCCACACCUCGCUCCCUGUUAGUGCCGUAUGACAGCCCCCAUCAAAUGACCUUGGCCAAGUCACGGUUUCUCUGUGGUCAAGGUUGGUUGGCUGAUUGGUGGAAAGUAGGGUGGACCAAAGGAGGCCACGUGAGCAGUCAGCACCAGUUCUGCACCAGCAGCGCCUCCGUCCUAGUGGGUGUUCCUGUUUCUCCUGGCCCUGGGUGGGCUAGGGCCUGAUUCGGGAAGAUGCCUUUGCAGGGAGGGGAGGAUAAGUGGGAUCUACCAAUUGAUUCUGGCAAAACAAUUUCUAAGAUUUUUUUGCUUUAUGUGGGAAACAGAUCUAAAUCUCAUUUUAUGCUGUAUUUUAUAUCUUAGUUGUGUUUGAAAACGUUUUGAUUUUUGGAAACACAUCAAAAUAAAUAAUGGCGUUUGUUGUA